GUCACUGCCGAGGAAUGAAGAGAGGCGGCCGGGCCCCGCGCUCCGCCCCGGCCUAGGGCCUUGCCCCGGGAGCCCGCGAGGGUAACGGAGCCCCCCGUCCUGACACCGUCCCCCGUCUGCUCCCGCCCCUCCCGGCUUCUCAGACUCGCAAACUCUGCUCCUCAGAUCGCCACUGUCCCCUUUCUCCUUUCUGAAUCUGUUUCACCCGAAGCCAUCUCCCCUCGGCACUCCUUUCUCGCCCUGACUGCUCCUUGCUUCGUCCCGAUCUUUCCUCCUCCCUUUCACCUGCGUCCUGCGUUCCUACCCCGCGCUCUCCAGCUCCCGGCCUCCCUUCCUGAGCUGUGCUGGCCAGUUUGGACGGUCCCCCCUUGUCAGCUAGACUUUCGGGAGGGAUGGUGGAGUUUUAAGGUGAUUAAGAUGCAGUGUAUUAUCCCCACAGUAGGAUAAAGUUCAUUUAAAAUCUCAAUAUAAUACUAAAAUGAAAAGCAAAUAAGCUUAUUCUUCCUAUUGAUAGCCAAACUAAGGUGCAUACAGUAAUGGAGGAAAGGCGAGAAAAAGGUGUGUGUGUGUGUUUGUGUGUGUGUGUGAGAGAGGGAGAGAGACGGAGGUUGACGGAUUCUAGGGCAGUCUUAAGAACUUUAGAAAAAAGAAAAGUUGCCAUGAGCCGAUGGAAACUUUAGAAGCUGAUGAUGAGUAAGCCGGGGGCUGCGUGAUCUCACUCUUCUCAUAAUUACUAGGUUAACGGUGUGGCUCCGGUCGGGAUGGAAUGGGAUUUGUUUACUGGGCCGGCGUAUUUUUAGCUUGUCGGCUCACAAGGACCAGCGCUCAGAGUCUCUUUCUCCCCGCUCGUGGUAGUCUUUCUUGUCUAACCUAGGUGGCUUCUCUGGGCACAAUAAAGAUGUAAAAAUUUGAAAUUAGAAACUGACUGGUGGAAUUUUAUGGAAGAAGUUCCCCACAAACUUUUCAGGCAGCUUUUCACGAAUGCAAAGCCUAGAAUUAGCAGGACGUUGACUUUUAUUUUCCUUAUCUUUUUAUACGUACUACGUAACGCUUUGCUUAGAAAUUCACAUGCUGCUAAUUUUUCAGUCUUUGGCCUCUAGUACUGUAUAUUUAGGAGAUUUUUGAGGAGGCUGGAUCCCUUUGUCUUUCAGAAUCUAUUUCAAAGGUGGAAAAGGACAGAGUAGAGAAAGAGGUGGCGGUAAGACUGGCUCCAAAGAGUUGCUAACCCCUAAAUAUUUAAAAAAGUUUCUAUGCUAUGUAACUUCUGAAAACAUGUAGAAAAUUUUCUUCCUACUAAAUGAGAUUGCAUUCCUGAUGGGGAGAAGACUUCAGGGACGGAAGCUGGGUGGCUAGGGAGAAUCAGAGGUAGUUAAAUAUUUGCUGUGUAUAACUUACAAAUACAUUAUGCGCAAACAAUGAAGAAUUAAUUAUACGCUUUGUCUUCAUUGUUUUUCAAGUAGUUCUUUUAACGUUCAGUAACCAACCUGCUGUGCUAGUCUAUUGAUAUUUUGAAGGCUGAACAAAACUGUAAAAUAAAUGAACUUGAUGUUGCUCCUCUGCAGGCUGAAUACCCCCGACCGUUCUAAUUUCCACUAUUGACCCAGCUUGCCUCAGAGCACCUCCCUGACAAAGUGGCCAGUUACUAUGUACUUAGAGAUUGCAAAUCAAUGCAAAUAUUAGCUCAUACUAGGAAUAAUUAAGAAGGUAAAUAUGCUGAAAACAUAUAUUCCAAAACCAAAAUAGAUUUUUUCGAUUUUACCCUCAUUUUUGAUUAUCACCACCUUUCUGCCAAUAAUUAUCCGUUAACAUGAAUAAUUUAGAAUUGAACAGAUAUCUGCUUUGGACAUUACACUUUCAAGAUAGAAGGAAAGAUGGAAGGAAGAUAGUGCCAAACUAAUUUUUUAUUGUCAUUGCCUUAUUUGACUUAUUCCUUGCUUUUAAUACUGAAGACUCCCUCGGAAAAAAAUGUAAAACUUUGCCAAAGCAAGAGCUGGCUAUCUACUGACUUGUAUAAGGCCCGGUGACUGGUAAUGAAUGCUAAUCAUUAGGUGGCCUUUAGUGGCCUUAUGUUGCCAACAACUUGGAAAAUUUCCCAAAGCUUUAUUUGUUUAAUCUUUCUUUUGAGACCCCUAUUUAAAAAACGACUUAAUUUGGAGACGAAAAUCUAAUUUUUAAAAACCACAUACACCUUUCCCAGAAUCUGUUGAUGAUCAAUAAUUGUUUUGAUCUGUGUGAGUUGAUUGGUGCCAAUAUUAGUGAUGAUAUCUGGGUAAAUUCUAUUUAUAUCUGCAUCUAGCAACUCCCUAAGUUGAACUGCAUACUUUAUUCCAGGGCAUGGGGAUCAAAGGGGUUGAAGAAGCCUAGGAAUGAGUGGAGAGCUGCCUGGUAGUCCACCACUAUUCCUAGUUCUCAGGAGGCUUUAUUUGCAAUUUUGAGAUUCAAUGUAUGUAACCAAAAUAAGUAUUCUGAUUGUUAUGAGGGCACUAAGUGCCACUUGUCAAAGUUUUGGAGCUCCUGAGUAUCUUAAGCAUGCUAAAAGACACUGGCCAUUAUAGUGUGGGUGUAUGUGUGUAUGAGUAGCACUCUCCUUACCCUAAACACUCAUCCCACCAAAGGGAAAAUCCUUAAACAGCGCUUUGAAAUGUGACCUCAGCAGUAUCUUUCCUAUGGGAACUUAGGAGCUGUGGAAUAGCAGACUGUGGAAUCUUUUUUGUAGCCUCUGAUAAAUUCAGGUAAUUAAAAAUUUGUGUAACUGGAAGAUAGAUACAGGGCAGUUUUUCUCAUGAAUGCCUGAAUUCAGUUGACUUUUUAAUAUAAUAGAAGAGAGUUGUUUGUUUGUUUUUAAAUAAGACAUCCUUGCUGAGUAAUGAUUGAACACUUCUCUGGAUAAAGCAGUCUCCAUGCUCCAGUGACAGGCUUUAGGGAGGUAUAAAAGAUGUAAAGACAUGUGUCUUUGCUCUUGGGGUUGAGGGUGGAUGGGAAAGGUGGUGUAUAAAUAUGGGAAGGCAGACUAUUAUGAGCUUUAACAUUUAGGAAACAACAUAUAGACAAAAGCAAAUUUAACGUGCUGAUAAGUAUGUAAGGGCUGAGAAGACUUAAAGUAACAAAGUAAGAAUCAGUGAAAUAAAUUGGGGAGAUUUCUGAGUCAGUAAAUUUUGAAAUGGACUUGGGAGGCUAUGGAUGAGUCAUAAAGAGGUAUGGGCUAUUGAGUUAGAUGGGUCUUCGUUCAGACCUUGCGGCUAUUUUUUACCAUGUGACCUUGGACAAGUUAACUUCUUUUCCUUAUCUGUAAAAUGUGAGCAUUCAAGUAAAUGAAAUAGUUACUGUGUUGGGAAUAAAAGAAAAGAAAGGAUCUUCCAAACAGAAAGUAUAGAAUGUACAGUGUGCAAUGAUGAUAUGAAUGACUAAGUUGUGAGUGGGGGGAAUAUAUGAGAGUGACUGUAGAGAAUGUGGGUUGGGCAAGUCAUGAGUAGAGCAGGCAAGAGGGUGGAGGGGACUCAGAAGCCAGACUCUGUUGGGUGUUGAUAGAAGGGUCAAUAGAAUCAUUGUAGGUCCUUGAACAAAGGACGGAUUUAAUGAGAAAUAUUGAGCCCUUUGGUUCAGGAACUCAGGGACAAGGAAUCAGGCAGGCAUCCGUACAUUGUGACUCUUAUUUUCUGUACCAUCCUAACCUGAAGGGAUACAGCCAGGAGGCAUAAGAUUCCUUGUAGAAGUUUUUGUGUUUACACACCUUACUAUGCUGAGCCUGCUUGUUCCUGUCUCGUAGUGCACCAACCUGUGGGGAAGUCUCAAGACUAUGGCCGGAUUCUCCUCAAGAGCUUAUAGUGGAGGCCUGAAUUUUGAUCUAUGUUCUACCUACAUCCAGCUGGCUGAAAGUACUUGAGGAUCACAUGACCCUGGACAUGGAUGCUGUUCUGUCAGAUUUUGUCCGUUCCACAGGAGCAGAGCCAGGGCUAGCGCGAGAUCUCCUAGAAGGAAAGAAUUGGGAUGUGAAUGCCGCCCUCAGUGAUUUUGAACAGCUACGUCAAGUCCAUGCUGGAAACCUACCCCCAUCCUUUAGUGAGGGGAGUGGUGGCUCCAGGACCCCUGAAAAAGGGUUUUCUGACAGAGAGCCUACUCGCCCUCCCCGACCCAUCCUCCAGCGGCAGGAUGACAUCGUUCAAGAAAAACGCCUGUCUAGGGGCAUCUCCCACGCCAGCUCCAGCAUUGUUUCCCUGGCCCGGUCCCAUGUCUCCUCCAAUGGUGGGGGUGGGGGGAGCAAUGAGCACCCCCUGGAAAUGCCCAUCUGUGCCUUCCAGCUUCCAGAUCUCACUGUAUACAAUGAAGACUUCCGCAGCUUCAUAGAGAGAGACCUCAUUGAGCAGUCCAUGCUGGUUGCCUUGGAACAGGCAGGGCGUUUGAACUGGUGGGUGAGUGUGGAUCCCACCUCUCAGAGGCUGCUUCCUUUGGCAACUACUGGAGAUGGGAACUGCCUCCUGCAUGCAGCCUCCCUUGGAAUGUGGGGUUUCCAUGAUCGGGACUUGAUGCUGCGGAAAGCUUUGUAUGCACUGAUGGAGAAGGGAGUUGAGAAGGAAGCGUUGAAAAGGCGCUGGAGGUGGCAGCAGACACAGCAGAAUAAAGAGUCAGGGCUGGUAUACACAGAAGAUGAAUGGCAGAAGGAGUGGAAUGAACUGAUCAAGCUUGCCUCAAGUGAACCCCGAAUGCAUCUAGGUACCAAUGGAGCCAACUGUGGUGGGGUGGAGAGUUCUGAGGAGCCUGUAUAUGAGAGCCUUGAAGAGUUUCACGUCUUUGUCCUUGCUCAUGUGCUUAGGAGGCCCAUAGUCGUCGUGGCAGACACCAUGCUGAGGGACUCCGGAGGGGAAGCAUUUGCCCCUAUUCCCUUUGGAGGAAUCUAUCUGCCUUUGGAGGUCCCAGCCAGCCAGUGUCACCGCUCCCCUCUGGUGCUCGCCUAUGAUCAGGCCCACUUUUCUGCACUCGUGUCCAUGGAGCAGAAGGAGAAUACCAAGGAACAAGCUGUGAUCCCACUUACAGAUUCAGAGUAUAAGCUGCUGCCCUUGCACUUUGCUGUGGACCCUGGAAAGGGCUGGGAGUGGGGCAAAGAUGAUAGUGACAAUGUCCGAUUGGCCAGUGUAAUUCUGUCCCUAGAGGUCAAAUUGCAUCUGCUGCAUAGCUACAUGAAUGUGAAGUGGAUCCCACUGUCCUCUGAUGCACAGGUGAAGACUUCUCCCACAUCUACCCUGGCUCCUCUGGCCCAGCCUGAGUCCCCCACCGCCUCAGCUGGAGAUGAGCCCCGGUCCACUCCUGAGUCUGGAGACUCAGACAAGGAGUCAGUUGGCAGCAGUUCCACCAGCAACGAGGGCGGCCGGCGGAAGGAGAAGUCAAAGCGAGAUCGGGAGAAGGACAAGAAGAGAGCAGAUUCUGUGGCUAACAAACUGGGCAGCUUUGGCAAAACCUUGGGCAGCAAGCUCAAGAAGAACAUGGGGGGCCUGAUGCACAGCAAGGGUUCAAAGCCUGGAGGGGUGGGGACAGGGUUGGGAGGAAGCAGCGGCACUGAGACACUGGAGAAGAAGAAGAAAAACUCACUGAAGAGCUGGAAGGGUGGCAAGGAGGAGGCAGCUGGGGAUGGGCCUGUGUCUGAGAAGCCCCCAGCUGAGUCUGUUGGUAACGGAGGGAGCAAGUAUAGCCAGGAGGUGAUGCAGAGCCUGAGCAUUCUGAGGACUGCCAUGCAAGGGGAGGGGAAGUUUAUUUUUGUUGGAACCCUGAAGAUGGGUCACCGUCACCAGUAUCAGGAGGAAAUGAUCCAGCGCUACCUUUCUGAUGCUGAGGAGAGAUUCCUGGCAGAACAGAAGCAGAAGGAGGCAGAGAGGAAGAUCAUGAAUGGAGGAAUAGGGGGUGGCCCUCCUCCAGCCAAAAAGCCAGAGCCAGAUGCUAGGGAAGAGCAGCCGACCGGUCCCCCAGCAGAGUCCAGGGCAAUGGCAUUUUCCACUGGCUACCCUGGGGACUUUACUAUCCCUCGGCCGUCUGGGGGCGGAGUCCACUGCCAGGAACCCCGGAGGCAGUUGGCAGGGGGUCCAUGUGUCGGGGGCCUACCACCAUAUGCCACCUUCCCCAGACAGUGCCCUCCUGGGCGACCCUACCCCCACCAGGACAGCAUCCCUUCUCUGGAGCCAGGCAGCCACUCUAAGGAUGGACUUCACAGGGGUGCCUUGUUACCACCCCCCUACCGAGUGGCUGAUUCCUAUAGCAAUGGCUACAGAGAGCCCCCUGAGCCAGAUGGAUGGGCUGGAGGUCUCCGGGGCCUUCCCCCAACUCAGACCAAAUGCAAACAACCGAACUGCAGCUUCUAUGGACACCCUGAGACAAACAACUUCUGUUCCUGUUGUUACAGGGAAGAACUGAGGAGGAGGGAGCGGGAACCGGAUGGGGAGCUCCUGGUGCACAGGUUCUGAACGGGUGGAACACUGAAGGGCAAGGAGGCUAAACAAAGUUAAGCUCAACUAAUUGGCUCAUCAAGAACACAGUCCCCAUGUUGAGGGGGAAAAUGCAGUAAUGUUUGUGGGAGCCUGGCUGGAAACUUUUAAGUGUGUGCACACAGGAGUGCUGCCAGGCUGGCAAGAGCAGGUCGGGGCUGGAUGGCACCUCAGGGGCUGUACUAUUCCUCUGCAGAGCUUGACUUGAUGAGGUUUGAGGUACAAGGGGAAAAGAUGGCGAUUCUGUCUUAUAACCUCCUGGGUCCCAUCCAGGGACCUAAGAGAAAGUAGCAGGGGAAGGUUUGGUGUGUGGGGGUGGGAGGUGGGCAGAAGUCUUGGGGAGGAAUGGGCAAAGGAGGUUCUCAGUCAAUAAAACCAAAGUUCUUUAGGUUGGGAAAAAGCACAUGGUGGAGUGAGAAGUGUGGAGGGGAAGUGGGAAAUUGGACACAUUUGCUAUUGAUUUGAAUUAAGCUAGAAAUUAAGGUUGGAUAAAUUCUUCCCCUUGAAGGAUCUGGAAAGACAAGGCAGUAAUGUGUCCUCAUGGGUGCCUGUUAGGAGGUGGGGGUAGUUUAAAUCCGUUUGUUUAGAUGGGAAAGGGAGGAACUUAAGAGGGAAAUCCUUUUCCUCUUAAGGUUUAUUUCCUUCCAAGCAGUCAUAUGUCAUCUGUUACAGUUUGAGAAGAGAUUGCUGAUUACCCCCUGUCUUUUCCUCAUCUAAGUCUUUAAUUGUAUUUGUUUAAAGGGAAGAGUGUGGUGAGAACAGCCGUCAUGUGUGUUGCAUUUUCUCCAGGUGAAUUGGGGCAGAGCUGAUCUAUUUUUUAACCACAGCAAUAACCAUACGUUGGGGUUUGAGUGCACCUUGGGAGGGGUGGGAGGACAGACAUUUUAGCCAGAGGCUGUUUCAAACAAAACCAAAAACCUAAGUAGAGCAUUACAGGCCUCUGUGGCUGCUGCGUUUCUGUAGAAAGCAACUUAUUUUAUUGACUUUUUUUUUUAAGGAAAAGAAAUAAAAAGACCCCAGCAAGCAAAAACAUUUAAAAAAUGAUUUUUUUUCCUCCUACUUAAGUGGUUCUUUCUCCCUUUGCUCUACUUUUGGAGAAUGAACUUAACAUCCCGGCUUCUUUUGUUAAGCCAUAGCUGACCUUAAUCUGUGGUUAGUUUAUUAAAAUAAUUAAAAAUACUUUCUAAGAAGAGAUAUUUUUGAUAUUAGGACUGAUGUUGAAACAUAUAGGGGCAAUUUAUAAAAAGGUAGUUAGAGAAAUAUAUUUUAGUGAACUAUAACCACAGAGCACAGAUGACUCCCAAUGAGCUGAUCUGUCUUUAGGUUUCUCCCUUUCCCUGACCCUUCCCUGUUCUCUAGGGGCUGGGAGUGGGGAUGCGGACACAGUAGGGGGAGCUCCUUCGCAUUUUGCACAAAGCACAAGUCUGAACAGCCUAUGCUCUGGCCAGAGCCAUUUCUAAGAGCUUUAAACCGGAAGACCUAUCCUGGGCCAAUUUUCCUUUUUCUUUAUAUUUUUUUCCGGGAAAAAAAGUCAACUAUGCAAUUGUAUACACUCCCGGGUGCAUGUGAAGAAGGGGAAUAAGUGUACUUAUGUGUCCAGAGUAUUAACUGGGGCUGUUUUUCUGUGUUUGGAUUUCUCUUUUGAGGUAUGUACUCAUAACCCAUCCCUUGGAACGUAAUCCCCACAUUUGAUCUAAAGCACUUGAGCGUGCAUGCAUGUGCGUGCGUGCAUAUGUGUGUGUGUUUUCCUCCUCGGUAGCCAGUCAAGAUUGUCCUUGUUGGAAAUGCUCACGGUUUAUAAAGGUUAUUUUCUCCUCAACAAACUCAGAAGUCACCUAUUUUCCAAAUCUGAUUUAAUAAUUUCCUAUGGCUAUUAAUUCUUAGGGUUUUCUUUGAAAAUAGAUUUGUGUUAAGGAAGCAGUGAGAUUCCAAAGGAAGGGAUGUGUAUAUGUCUAGGCAGGUCUGGAACCUGGUAUGAGAUGAGCACUCCCCUAAGUUGCAAAAUUUAAGGGUUACUAUAAAACUCAUUAAUCAAGAUACUAUAAAAAAUGCAGUAUUUAAAAAAAUUAAUGCAAAAAAUUUAUGUUGGAUAAAAUAGCGAAAUCUUACAGGAUCUGACAGGACUGAGAUUAGGAGGAGGGAAGUGAGGCUGAAUUGAAUAAGUAUGGGGAUGAAUCCUUCUUAUUUAAAUUUUUGAUACAUUGUCCAUCAUAGACUUUUUACAUUAAUUGUGAUUUUUUAAAAAUGUUGCAUUAAAAUAGUAUUUAUCUUGGUUACUGGGUUUUUUGGCACUCCUUAAAUUUUGUGCCCAAGGUGAGUGCUUUGCUCACCUCACCCUAGUUACGUCCCUGUUUCUGUGAUUUGAACACUAGCGAGAACACCACUGUGUGCGCCUCCACCCCCAUCACACACCAAACAACAGGUGGCUCAGACACCCUGAAUUUGCACAGCUCACCUAGCUUUCCUAAUUUAGGCCUUCAUAUCAUAGAAUGGUGGCCUGGACCAAUAGGAAUGAAAACAGACCAGGGGUUUUCCCAGAGAAUAAAGCCGGAAAAGUUUUGAUUCUCCACUGGACUGCUGUGUUUGGAUUUGAUCUGUUGUUAGAUUCUAGUUAACACUUUUGUUUUUAAAAACUAAGGACAAAUGAACAAAAAACCUUGUAUCAUGUUUGUUUUUAUUUAUAAGUUAGCCAAUCCCAAUUCCGUUUGCUUUAUUUUCAAAUAAAAAAAGAUGGAAAUUUUGAGGGGUGGUCUAGGGGUGAAUAUGGUAAAAUGGGGCUUUAGGCCUUAUAGCUUUUUAUUAAGAAAUAAAUUAUUUUUUUUAUUUGGGAGGGUAACUAUUUAUUGAGGCAUUGAAAAACCUCUCCAUUCUAAGGAUGAGAGACCCUGAGACAAUGGAUAUUUUUUAUAGGAGAUAGUGAAGUUUGUUUUGCUUCAUUCUUUCGGGGAGGGUCUUGGUGGGAUGGGGGGAGGUGAAGGAAUAAUGCCUGGGAAAUUAAUAUAGAUUCAGCUUGGUUUGUGGUAUUUUGGGAAGAUGAGGGAAUAGAAGAGGCAAGCCCAUGUCGUUACUGGGUUGGGGAGAAGGAAAGAAGGGGCAUAUGGCCUGCACUCGAAAUGGGCAGAAAAAUUCCUUAGUUAAGGAGGGGUGUGUGAGUGAAGGGGGAAGGUAGACCCUUUAACCCCAAGUGAGGGAUGAUAUCAUCUCUCAGGCUUAAAUUUAAGUGCACUUAGUUCCUUUAAUCCAGGGCAACUGGGGUACCUACUGAAGUUUUUAAUGGAGAGGGGAGAUUUUCAGGGUUCUUGUUUUUCCCUUUUUGAUGUUAGACAGUGCUACUCCCUCCCUGCUGUGCUCUCUGCCCCAUCUCCAAUGGAGUAAGUAUUACUGUAGGAUAGGCCUCCGCUUCUCCCUUAACCUAUGCUGCAUUUAUUGAAAGUUACAAGAUUUAACCAGAAGUUUUUCCUCCAUACUGGUUUUUAUCAACAAAAUAAAAAGAUUAUAUCCAAAGAUUUUUUAAAGAUUCAGUCUUUUUAAGGAGUGGAGAUGGUGUUAAACUCAGUGCUGUAGAGGGCAGUGGAAGGGAAGUACCUUCCCUCUAUUAGCUCAGUUUUUUUUUUUCUAUCAAGCGAAACUAAGGCCCACAGACAAACAAGAAUUAGCAGUGACUUCGUGUUGUAUAUCUGCGGGGUGAUACUGAGCCCAAAAGAAUAAAGCUGGUUUUGAAUGUGUUCUGAGAACCUAGCUUUUGCCAUUCUUAACUCCUUUUAGCCAUGUGUCCAAGGUUCCAGUCACAUUUUUUUUUCUCAAUAAAGAGUAUUUCAGAGAUGAUUGUCUCUGAAUUACUCAGACACCUCUGGACUCUGAGUCUUCUUUCUUUUUCCUUUUUCUUUCUUUCUUUUUUUUUUGGUUUGAGACGGAGUCUCGCUCAGCUGCCCAGGCUGGAGUGCAGUGGUGCAAUCUCGGCUCACUCCAACCACCGUCUCCUGGGUUCAAGUGAUUCUCCUGUCUCAGCCUCCCAGGUGGCUGGGAUUACAGGCACCCGCAAUCAUGCCCGGCUAAUUUUUGUAUUUUAGUAGAGAUGGGGUUUCACCAUGUUGGCCAGGCUGAUCUUGAACUCCUGACCUCAGGUGAUCCGCCAGCCUCGGCCUCCCAAAGUGCUGGGAUUACAGGCAUGAGCCACCGCGACUGGCCUCUGUGUCUUCCUUCUCCAAUGAGUCAGUGCCCCAGACAUAUAGCCACAGGUGAGAAGACAGAAUUAGAAGCCCCUUCCCGGCCUGGAAUCACCUGCACUCCAGAUUUUUCUAAUUUCCUUCUUUCCCUCCAGGCCUUUCAACUAUAGAUCUGGAUGAGUCAUGCAGGCAUUCUGUCUCUUCUACUUUGCAGACAGCCAGUCUGCAAAUCACAGGGUAUUUUGCCACCAUACAUCAGUUGGGUAACAAAAUAUUACGAUGUCCCCAUGUAGACUUUCUCUGUGCCAUCUCUUGCAUUGGCCAAGUGGGUAAGGGGCAGUACAAAAGAGCAACGGAAGCUGGCUGGCAGCAGUUAAGAGGAGUAGGGGUGGGAAGGACCUUGGCCUCUUUCUGUGCUUAUAACUGGAUCUGUGACUCAUCUUGUGAGUCACUCAGCUCCACCUCCCUCCUCCGGCUGCCCCUCCCAGCAGCCUUUACUCCUGGCACAAACCUGCAGCCAGAACAGGAUUCUGAAAAUGGAAAAAUCUGAUAUAGCCCCUUGCCUCUCCACCCUUCCCUUCAUCUAGUGCUUCUACUGGGGGUGUGUGGGGUGGUGAGAGGCAGCCUUAACCCUCAGCUCCUGCCCACUCCAUUCCUGGUUAAGUAUUGAUCCAAAUCGCCCAAUUCUUUUCUCCUCCUGAUUUCCCCCCACCCCGCUUUUUUUUUUUUUUUUUUUUGAGACAGAGUUUCGCUCUUGUCGCCCAGGAUGGAGUGCAAUGGCGCGAUCCCGGCUCACUGCAACCUUCGUCUCCUGGGUUCAAGCGAUUCUCCUGCCUCAGGCUCCCGAGUAGCUGGGAUUACAGGAGCCUACCACCAUGCCUGGCUUAAUUUUUUUUUUUUUUUUUUUUUUUAGUUAGAGUCGGGGGUUUCGCCAUGUUGGCCAGGCUGGUCUUGAAUUCCUAACCUCAGGUGAUCCGUGAUCCACCCACCUCAGCCUUCCAAAGUGCUGGGAUUACAGGCAUGAGCCACCACACCCCUACCCCCCGAUUUUUUUUCUCCGUGUUCCUCCACUGUCUCCACACCUCAAAGUGCUAAAGAAUAGAAUGAGGCUCUUGAAUGAAGGAUGGUGGUGAGAAGGAAAGUGGAUAAUGGGAUUUAAAAGUUAUGGUACACACCUCUUCCUAUGUCUUUUUUUUUUUUUUUUUUUUUGCGAUGGAGUCUUGCUCUGUUGCCCAGGCUGGAGCGUAGUCAUUAGAUCUUGGCUCACUGCAACCUCUGCUUCCUGGGUUCAAGCGAUUCUCCUGCCUCAGCCUCCCAAGUAGCUGGGAUUAUAGGUGUGAGCCACCACGCCUGGCUAAUUUUUGUAUUUUCAGUAGAGAUGGGGCUUCAUCAUGUUGGCCAGGUGGUCCUGAACUCCUGACCUCAAGUAAUCUGCCUGCCUUGGCCUUCCAAAAUGCUUGGGAUUACAGGCGUGAGCCACUGCGCCUGGUCCCUAUUUUCUUUUUACAACAGACCUUGGGAAAUAUUUUCUUCCCCCAAGAGGUUGAGGCCCAUGGAAUGCAUUAGGGGCAGGUGGGGUGGUGGUGCUCUGUAGCCUUUAGGACUUCUAGAAUCAGGCUUCUGGGCCACCUUCUUAGCAGGUGUAUACCUCUUUGUUCCAGACUGACUUUCUGUCUCACAAUAUCUUCACUAUUUCCACAGUUGCAGCCAAGACAGGAAACUGAAAGCUGAGGCCAGAAGGGUGGUGUACUGGGGGGAGGGGAAAAUUGAGUGUCACUUUGGAAAACUGGGGCCCCCAUCUAAGGAUUGCUGCCUCUGUAGAUUCAAAAGCAAUAAAACAGCAGCUCAUUAACUCUUA